GCAACUUGGUCUCACAGUGGCUUAGGCCAGGGUGGGAGCAGUGAACGGAGUCACAAAAGAAAUUUUUCAGGUAGCAUUCACGGGUGGGUGCUGGAUUAGAUGCAGGGCUAAGGGCAGGGGAGGAAGCCUGGGUAAUGGAAGGCUGCGGGGCCAAGGGGGGACUGGGAAUCCUGGAGGGCCAGGUCUGGGGGAGAGUUAGGAGGUCGUGAAUUUGGACUUGGAUGCUUGUUGAAGCUGAUGCAUCUUGAGGACAUUUGUGGGACACAUAGGCUGGGUCAGGGCUGAAAGAGGUGCUGGUUAUGGCCGGGGGCAGGGACUCAUGCCUGUAAUCCCAACAGCCCAGGAGGAUGAGACAGGAGGAAUGCUUGAGGCCAAAAUUUCGAGGCCGGAAGUUCCAGACGAGCCUGGGCAACACAGCAAGACCCUGUCUCUAGAAAAGGAAAGAAAGAACCGCUGGUUGUGGAAGCCAGCCAUGGCCCAGAGCUCAGCAGUGUAGGAGAGGAGGGUGCGGGCCUGAGAGAGGCAGCAGGCUUGGCUGGAGAGGCAGAAGGAAAACCAAGGCAGGAGAGUGUCCUGGAAGCUGGGAGAAGGCAGAGGGAGAUCGAGGCUUACUUUCUGGCUGAGGGGCCUAGGCUGUCCUCUCUGACACCACCCCGGCCUGCCUCUUUGUUGCCAUGAGAGCUGCCUACCUCUUCCUGCUAUUCCUGCCUGCAGGCUUGCUGGCUCAGGGCCAGUAUGACCUGGACCCGCUGCCGCCGUUCCCUGACCACGUCCAGUACACCCACUAUAGCGACCAGAUCGACAACCCAGACUACUAUGAUUAUCAAGAGGUGACUCCUCGGCCCUCCGAGGAACAGUUCCAGUUCCAGUCCCAGCAGCAAGUCCAACAGGAAGUCAUCCCAGCCCCAACCCCAGAACCAGGAAAUGCAGAGCUGGAGCCCACAGAGCCUGGGCCUCUUGACUGCCGUGAGGAACAGUACCCGUGCACCCGCCUCUACUCCAUACACAGGCCUUGCAAACAGUGUCUCAACGAGGUCUGCUUCUACAGCCUCCGCCGUGUGUACGUCAUUAACAAGGAGAUCUGUGUUCGUACAGUGUGUGCCCAUGAGGAGCUCCUCCGAGCUGACCUCUGUCGGGACAAGUUCUCCAAAUGUGGCGUGAUGGCCAGCAGCGGCCUGUGCCAAUCCGUGGCGGCCUCCUGUGCCAGGAGCUGUGGGAGCUGCUAGGGUGGUGCUGGCAUCCUGAGUCCUGGCCCUCCUGGGAUCUGGGGCCCUCGGGCCCUGCCUGACCUGGUGCUUUUUUCCCCAUCCCCAUGUUCCUUUUAUUCUGUAAAAAGUUAGUGGACUGCAGCCCUGGGGGUUGCAGGCUGCGGUGCCUCAGGCCCCUCCUUCAGCCUGUGGCCACCUCUGGGGCACAAUGGGGGCUCCCCACUGCCCAGUCUGCCCCUCGGGUUGGGGGAGUAUCCCAGGCCUCUCUGUGGGACCUGGGCCCCUGACGGGCCUUCUCAGCCCGUUUUGAGGACAGACAGUCCCCCGAGGUAGGCUACAUCCCCCCACCCCAGCUGGUCUGCUUGGAUUUCCUACAGCCCCCGUGGGCAUGGACCACCUUUAUUUUAUACAAAAUUAAAAACAAGUUUUUACAAAA